UGCCUGCGCCUGAGCCUCUACGAGAGGGAAGGAACGCUGCUCCGAGCUCCGCGUCGCGUCGCGUAGAUUCGCGUCGCCGUCGACCUCAGAGGCGGGGCCGGAAGCGCUACGGUUUGACCCCCGAGUCCCUCUGUUCCCGAAGGGGCGGCCGUCUUUCUCCCGACCCGCUCCGCCUCCUCUCCUUCUUCCCCAUUACCCGGAGGCCGAAGCCCCCAGCCAGGGCGGGGCGGCGCAGCCCGAGCUCCCGGACCCGGAAGAAGCGCCAUCUCCCGCCUCCACCAUGGAGCCCACCGCACCGUCCCUCACCGAGGAGGACCUCACUGAAGUGAAGAAGGACGUGAGUAACGCAGCUGUGCCCAGGGCGGGCGGGGGCGGGCUGCAGCCCAGCGGGAGACGAAAGCGGAAGCCUGGAGUCCGAGGACAAGGAGGAUCCUCCAGGUCGGAGGAGCGGAAAGUCCUAGCACAGGAGGACUGUGGCGAGCCCUGCAUCCGAGGGACCUUGGUGGCAGUGAUCCUCCAGUGAUCUGUCAAUCCAGGUUUUACAUCGCUAAACGCAGAGCUUGGGCUUUGUUGCCAAGUGGUGUUUUGAUUCUUGCCCACUCCUCACCCAUCUCCUCAUGCUUUCCCCCCAACUGGGUUCUUGGAGAUGCUUCGUUAGGGACUGGCGGCUCAGAUUCAUCCUUAAGUCAGGCUGCCUAGGCUGCUCACUCAGCCUAGAGCGAAGGCUGUACCAGGUGAAGGAUCCCAAGCAGUGGACCAAAAAUGUGAAGCUCUUUUGCAUAAGGGGGCUUGAGGAAGCUCAACAGCUGAAAGCACAACCUGGAAUUCCCCUAGUAAGCAGACGCCCACAUAUUUAAAUUGGGGUUGGGGGAGUGAAUACACGUAGCUGAGAAUUAAUGUACAGGUAAACGUCGAAAAUAUUCAGUAGCUAAAUUAUGCUCUUCUCGGAUGGUGCAGAACCACAUAAACCUUCAUAUUUAUUCGUAACGAAUGGCUUUGUUGAGAUAUGACAUUCUUUUUCCUUUGCGUUUACUUGUUUUGUCAGAUGAGACCUAUAUGAGUAUCACUAAAAUACUUUAUCUGAAGUCAAAUGAAAAACAGAAACUCAACAUGAAACGUGUUCUUAUUGAACACUGCAGUACUUUUACAAAGUCAUUUUGAUGAACUGGACAGGAUGGCAACUUUUUAAAUGUUCAUCCACUUCAAAUCCCUUCCUCUUCCCUGUAAGGUUUAUUACACUGUACUCACAAUUGGUGUGACUCACCAGCAGAAGGAAACUGGAUAUGACUGGGAGUUGUGCUUAGUUUCCUCAUUCAACAGAGAUUUAUGGAGCACUUGCUAUAUGGAAAGCACUGGCCUUGGGUCUGGAAGGAUACAAAAAAAUGAAGAUCAGUUUCCUGCUUUACAUUCUAGUUGAGAUAAGAAUGGAACAUAAAUAACUACUGUAGAAUAAAUGUUGUCUUAUUCAUGGCCUUAGAAAAUUUACGUGUAUACCUGUGUGAGAAAAUCAUAGCUGAGAGACAUUUUGAUCAUCUACGUGCAAAAAAAAUACUCAGUAGAGAAGACACUGAAGAAAUUUCUUGUCGAACAUCAAGUAGAAAAAGGGCUGGAAAAUUGUUAGACUACUUACAGGAAAACCCAAAAGGUCUGGACACCCUUGUUGAAUCUAUUCGGCGAGAAAAAACACAGAACUUCCUGAUACAGAAGAUUACAGAUGAAGUGCUGAAACUUAGAAAUAUAAAACUAGAACAUCUGAAAGGACUAAAAUGUAGCAGUUGUGAACCUUUUCCAGAUGGAGCCACGAACAACCUCUCCAGAUCAAAUUCAGAUGAGAGUAAUUUCUCUGAAAAACUGAGGGCAUCCACUGUCAUGUACCAUCCAGAAGGAGAAUCCAGCACGACGCCCUUUUUUUCUACUAAUUCUUCUCUGAAUUUGCCUGUUCUAGAAGUAGGCAGAACUGAAAAUACCAUCUUCUCUUCAACUACACUUCCCAGACCUGGGGACCCAGGGGCUCCUCCUUUGCCACCAGAUCUACAGUUAGAAGAAGAAGGAACUUGUGCAAACUCUAGUGAGAUGUUUCUUCCCUUAAGAUCACGUACUGUUUCACGACAAUGACACUUUAUUGCCUUUUAAUUUUUAAUGAUGACAAAAAAUGUUUUAAAGAAUAUGACUUUUUAUAAAAUGGCUGUAAUCAUUUGUUUACAUUUGAUGCAUGUCUUUUAAAAUGCAAUGUAAGCAUACUUUGUAAAUAGGAUUUUUAGAAUUAAAAAAGCAUACUUCUAGGAUAGCUAACUGUAAAUCAUGUUGAUCAUGUACUUUUUAGUAAUUUCUUUUUUUCCUUUUUAAGGUCUUUCAGUACUUUUUUAAAUAUUUUCUAUUUUAAGACUGAUUUUAAUAGGGAAUAUAUCUCUAUUUGAGAAUAGACCCUUACUAGGAAGAACGUUUUUUCCUCAGUGCAUUUGUGCUAGAAAUUUUCAAGAGUCUAAUAGUCUUUGCCAGUCAUUCAGCAGCAAAUUUUCAGCAUUAAGCUGUUCCUGUUCAGUAAUAAAACCGGUCACUGAUGGGAAAACUGCCAAUAUAGAAAAAUAAAAAUCUCUUUUCCACUCCAUUGUCGUAUAGGCAUGUAAACAGCCUCUUUUUGAUACUGGAGGAACACUUGAUGGAGUGUGAGCCACCUAAGAUCUCGGUUUGCCAAAAUUCAUUUCUAAUUAACCUUACUAAUUAUACUACUUUGUUAGGAUUUUCACAUUCUUGGCUUAAUCAUUUUCAUUCCUAAAGAAAAAUAUCUUGGCCUAAACCUCAGUUAUUACAUGUAAUUUGAUGAGGUAUUUUUUCCUUUUUUCUUUUUUUUUUUUUUUUUUUUUUGAGACAGUCUUGCUCUAUCGCCCAGGCUGGAGUGCAGUGGCGCAUUCUAGGCUCACUGCAACUUCUGCCUCCCAUGCUUACGUGAUCCUCUCACCUCAGCCUCUCAAGUAAUAUAGCUGAGACUACAAGUGUGUGCCACCAUGCCUCACUAAUUUUUGUAUUAUUUUUGUAGAGACGGUGUUUUGCCAUGUUGGCCAGGCUGGUCUUGAACUCCUGGACUCAAGCAACCUACCCAGCGUGGCCUCCCAAAGUGCUGGGAUUACAGACACGAGCCACCUCACCUAGCCUGAUGAGAUUUUUAAAAAAUAUUUUCUCUGUACUUUUCAUUCUCUUUUAAUGAGGACCAAUGUACAGUUGAAAUAACUGGAACAAAUUAUUUUUGGUGUGUGUGACAAUUCUGUUUUUAAUGCUAUUUGAACAAGUGGGCCAUUAGCCAGAUUUGUCUUUUUGUUGUAAAACAAAAUUUGACUAAUUUUACAUGUUUAUAAAUCUUAUGCUCUCACUGUUUGUUUUUAUUUAAAUUACAAUUUUAUCUGUUUCCUGACAUUGUCUCCUAUAUAUUUCUAUUAUUAAUUGCAAAAACAUAGAAAUGGAAAUUUUGCUAUCAACAAUAAAAUUUUUUUAAAGUAGUGAGUGCUAUUUUGGAGUUCCAAAUUUUCAGUAGGAAGUAUCUAAAACUUUUUUUAAUACGUGCCAUUAUCUAUAGAAAACAUUACUUCAGGUUGUGAGAUUGAGUUGCAUUUCUGGAUGGACUGAUGAAUUUAUCCGACAUGAAGAAGAUUGGCAUAUUAGCUUUAAAAAUUUUUAAAGAUUGGAUUUUUUUUAGUAUAAGCACUUUCUAAGGAUUAUAGAGAAAUGUUUCACCUCCAAUGCAUAGCAAAAAUAGUGGUGUUAGAAAGAAAAUAGGUUACAUUUAAGGAAGGUGCUUUAAAAAGCAGAAGCAGACUUUAAAAUUAAAUUUGUGGACACCUUUUUAAAAAUUGAAUCAAAGAUUAUAAUUUAGAUAUACAAUAACACCUAUAUAUAGAUAAGUUUUAACACUGAGUUUUCUUUCAGACUGUUUUCUAACUACAUAGACAAUAAAAUUAAGCUUUGCAUAAA